AGGGACUGUUAGGAAAGGCAGGCAAACAGAGUGAGUGUGACCACCCAGAGCCUCUCACGCCGGCUCUGCACACGCCAGGCUUUUAUCCCCACCUCCACAUUGCAGCUAUCGCAGUUCUUCCACUGGAAAUGCCAGCUGUCAUGCCCCAUCCCUAUCUGUCCAUUCCCCAAGGCCAGCCCCAGGCCCCUCGCCACAGAAGCUCUCCCUGCCUGACCCACCCGGCUCCACCGGCUUUGAGUGCACGCAGCUCCGUUUGGCCCACCCUUUGAGGCCUGCGCACCUUUGACUUGGACUUGUGAAUUCAGGGCUAAACCUUGGACCUCAGACAGUUUCCCAGGAACCCUCCCAUCACCCCCACCACCCCAAACCCACACUUUUUCCCCCUCCCCACGCCAAGCCUCUCUUUCUCCAGCAGGGGGCAGCAAUUUAAUUUAAACCAACCCGAUGUGACAGCUGAAGUUGACUUAGCGCACGUAGGAUGUGAGCAAGGUGCCUACUUAUGUGUGCAGCCAGCACCCAGGCAGGGGGCUGAGGGGGAGGGGCGGACACAGAGGUAAAGUCACAGAACCAGAUCCAGCUGCCCCUCGGAACUCUUGAACAUUUUCUCUGAUGCUGGAUUGAAUUGAAGACCUGGGACCUGCUCCAUCCCUACAGCUCAAAGACAGCUCAGGGUGGACACUCACAGAGGUCAGAGGGAGCCGGGCCCUGGGAGUCCUAAGCCCAGCCCAUGUGGGUCUGGACAAGUCACUGCCCUUUUCAGGCCUUGAUUUCCUCCUCUACAUGGAGGAGGAUACUGAUUUCCAGCUUUGUGCAUGAAAUAUGAACAUGGCCCAAAAUCCCAGCAAGAAGAAUGUUAGGUAAGCUCUGGGACAGGACACUCUAUACCAUUCAGAGGAACGCCUCAGAGACAGAGUUAACGCCUGAUCCUCGAAACCAUGCCAUUUGCAACAGUGAUGAACGCAACGGUGCAGAAGACGUGGCCAGCUGUGGCUGUGACAGUGCACCAGGCUGGCCACUGCUGACGCACGUGCAAUGCUGGGCCUCACUUCAAAACCCUUUCUUUCCAAGUCACUGAGCCCUACUGCUGUGCGCCAAGGGCUGUGAUAUGGACCAACGGUGAGCAAAGCUGGCAGGGUGUCUACUCUCCUCACCUCCAGCCAAGUGAGAGACACAGACAAACAGAUGCAGCAUCACAAACUCUGGAGGAAAGAAAUGAGUGUGUGUGUGGGGGCCGGGGUGGGGGGGCGCUGACCUAGUUAAUGUGGGGUCAGAGAAGUAGGGUCUUCUGAGGAUGCGAUGUUUCUGCUGAGUCCUAAUGAGCUGACCAGGCGCAUGGAGUACAGGAGAAGUGCACUAGGCAAAGGAUGCGGCCCGAGCAAGAGCCCUGCAGAGAGAGCUGGCUUGGAGCAGAUCAGGAGGCACUGAGUGGGAGGGCAGUAGAGGAUGGGGCUAGAGAGAUGGGCAGGGCCCAGACCAGGCAUGGCCUUAUUGGCCACAGUGGAGAUGUUGGGCUUCAUUUUCCCCUGUCAUUUGUGCCAUCUGAGUCUCAAACUAGCCCAGCUUCCCAUUUCACAGCCAGAAAACUGAGGCUUGGAGUCAUUAUAAACAAACAAACAAACAAAAAUAACAACUAGCCAAAAGACAGGCAAAAAGCAAGGGAUGGAGAAUUCAGUCUUGUCAUUCCCAGGUCAGCGCUUAUUACAUAACCGUGAGCUUCCUCCAGCUGCAAUAUUAGGAGAUUCUCUUACAGAGAAAUCGGGGGGCUGCCCGCCAGAUGAUGGGCCCUGCCUCCUAUCGGUGCCUGACCAGUGCGUGGAAGACAGCCAGUGUCCCUUGACCAGGAAGUGCUGCUACAGAGCUUGCUUCCGCCAGUGUGUCCCCAGGGUCUCUGUGAAGCUGGGCAGCUGCCCAGAGGACCAACUGCGCUGCCUCAGCCCCAUGAACCACCUGUGUCACAAGGACUCAGACUGCUCGGGCAAAAAGCGAUGCUGCCACAGCGCCUGCGGGCGGGAUUGCCGGGAUCCUGCCAGAGGCUAAUUCUGAUUUAGGAUCUGUGGCUCUGCACCUAAGCUGGGGACCAACGGAAAGAGUUCACGAUGGGAGGCCUGGGGCCCUGCCCGCUGGACAGCACUAUCUCUACCAGCGGUGGUUCCAGCCUUCUGAUAAUCACUGGCCUGCUGACACUUCCCUGCAACCCAUCCACCCCUGGUUUCUCCUCCUGGGAGUCAAAGUCCAUAGCCUGAGCUCGGAGGAAGGCCUCUGUAUCACCCCAGUACUCUGCACCACUGCCAUACGAGCUUCCCACCCUUCCUAACGCUUUCACACCAAUCCGUACAUGCUGCUUCCUCCACCAAAAAUGCCCAAUUCAGGCAGACCCUGACCUCUCCCUCAGGCAGCCCAACCAUCCAGAAUGAAUAUUCUUGCAGAGUUUUCCAAACAUCAGUCAUUCACCUCUUUCAUGAUUUUCACCAUACCUACAAAAUAGCACCAUGAUAGGUUGCACGCUGCCUGUACCACCAUUUACUUAAUGUUUUCUUUAAAUGGCUCACUUUUGUAUAUAAAUAAAUUCAUUUCAAAAGAAAA